AUAGUUCGCGUAGCGGCUCGAGCGUGGAGAUGAAGCGUAUUUUCUCACUGCUAGAAAAGACUUGGCUUGGCGCACCAAUACAGUUUGCCUGGCAAAAAACAUCAGGAAACUACCUUGCAGUAACAGGAGCUGAUUAUAUUGUGAAAAUCUUUGAUCGCCAUGGUCAAAAAAGAAGUGAAAUUAACUUACCUGGUAACUGUGUUGCCAUGGAUUGGGAUAAAGAUGGAGAUGUCCUAGCAGUGAUUGCUGAGAAAUCUAGCUGCAUUUAUCUUUGGGAUGCCAACACAAAUAAGACCAGCCAGUUAGACAAUGGCAUGAGGGAUCAAAUGUCUUUCCUUCUUUGGUCAAAAGUUGGAAGUUUCCUGGCUGUUGGAACUGUUAAAGGAAAUUUGCUUAUUUAUAAUCAUCAGACAUCUCGAAAGAUUCCUGUCCUUGGAAAACAUACUAAGAGAAUCACUUGUGGAUGUUGGAAUGCAGAAAAUCUGCUUGCUUUAGGUGGUGAAGAUAAAAUGAUUACAGUUAGUAAUCAGGAAGGUGACACGAUAAGACAGACACAAGUGAGAUCAGAGCCUAGCAACAUGCAGUUUUUCUUGAUGAAGAUGGAUGACCGAACCUCUGCUGCUGAAAGCAUGAUAAGUGUGGUGCUUGGCAAGAAAACUUUGUUUUUUUUAAAUCUGAAUGAACCAGAUAACCCAGCUGAUCUUGAAUUUCAGCAGGACUUUGGCAACAUUGUCUGCUAUAAUUGGUAUGGUGAUGGCCGCAUCAUGAUUGGUUUUUCAUGUGGACAUUUUGUGGUCAUUUCUACUCAUACUGGAGAGCUUGGUCAAGAGAUAUUUCAGGCUCGUAACCAUAAAGAUAAUCUAACCAGCAUUGCAGUAUCACAGACUCUUAACAAAGUUGCUACAUGUGGAGAUAACUGCAUUAAAAUCCAAGACUUGGUUGACUUAAAAGACAUGUAUGUUAUACUCAACCUGGAUGAGGAAAAUAAAGGAUUGGGUACCUUGUCCUGGACUGAUGAUGGCCAGUUGCUAGCACUCUCUACCCAAAGGGGCUCACUUCAUGUUUUCCUGACCAAGCUUCCCAUACUUGGGGAUGCCUGCAGCACAAGGAUUGCCUAUCUCACCUCCCUCCUUGAAGUCACCGUAGCCAACCCUGUUGAAGGAGAGCUACCAAUCACAGUUUCUGUUGAUGUGGAACCCAACUUUGUGGCAGUAGGUCUUUAUCAUCUGGCUGUAGGAAUGAAUAAUCGAGCUUGGUUUUAUGUCCUUGGAGAAAAUGCUGUGAAAAAAUUGAAAGAUAUGGAGUAUCUGGGAACAGUAGCCAGUAUUUGCCUUCAUUCUGACUAUGCUGCUGCACUUUUUGAAGGCAAAGUCCAGUUACAUUUGAUAGAAAGCGAAAUCUUGGAUGCUCAAGAAGAACGUGAGACUCGGCUUUUCCCAGCAGUGGAUGAUAAGUGCCGUAUCUUAUGCCAUGCCUUAACUAGUGAUUUCCUCAUCUAUGGUACAGAUACUGGUGUCGUUCAGUAUUUCUACAUUGAAGACUGGCAAUUCGUUAAUGAUUAUCGACAUCCUGUCAGUGUGAAAAAGAUUUUUCCCGACCCAAAUGGGACCAGAUUAGUUUUCAUUGAUGAAAAAAGUGAUGGAUUUGUUUACUGUCCAGUCAAUGACGCUACCUAUGAGAUUCCAGAUUUUUCACCAACCAUUAAAGGUGUUCUUUGGGAAAACUGGCCAAUGGAUAAAGGUGUAUUUAUUGCUUAUGAUGAUGAUAAGGUGUACACUUAUGUCUUUCACAAGGACACUAUACAAGGAGCCAAGGUUAUUUUGGCUGGUAGCACCAAAGUUCCUUUUGCUCAUAAACCUUUGCUGCUAUAUAAUGGAGAGCUGACCUGCCAAACACAGAGUGGAAAAGUAAACAACAUCUACCUUAGCACCCAUGGCUUUCUCAGCAACUUAAAAGAUACGGGGCCUGACGAACUGAGACCAAUGCUGGCACAGAAUUUAAUGCUAAAGAGGUUUUCUGAUGCUUGGGAAAUGUGCAGGAUUCUGAAUGAUGAGGCUGCCUGGAAUGAGUUGGCCAGAGCUUGUCUACAUCACAUGGAAGUGGAGUUUGCAAUCCGUGUUUAUCGGAGAAUUGGAAAUGUUGGCAUAGUGAUGUCCUUGGAACAAAUAAAGGGAAUAGAGGACUACAAUCUUUUGGCAGGACACCUUGCCAUGUUUACCAACGAUUAUAACCUGGCUCAGGACUUGUACCUUGCAUCCAGCUGUCCUAUUGCUGCCCUGGAGGUAUGGCAGCAAAUGAGAAGGGAUUUACAGCAUUGGGACAGUGCUCUACAACUGGCAAAGCAUUUGGCCCCAGACCAGAUACCUUUUAUAUCAAAAGAAUAUGCUAUUCAGCUUGAAUUCGCGGGUGAUUAUGUAAAUGCUUUGGCUCAUUAUGAGAAAGGAAUAACAGGUGAUAAUAAGGAACAUGAUGAAGCUUGUCUGGCUGGAGUGGCCCAGAUGUCCAUAAGAAUGGGAGACAUACGUCGAGGGGUUAACCAAGCCCUCAAGCAUCCCAGCAGGGUCCUUAAAAGAGACUGUGGAGCCAUAUUGGAGAAUAUGAAGCAAUUUUCAGAAGCGGCCCAACUGUAUGAAAAAGGUCUCUACUACGAUAAAGCAGCAUCUGUUUACAUCCGCUCUAAGAAUUGGGCAAAAGUUGGUGAUCUUCUGCCCCACGUUUCUUCUCCUAAGAUCCAUUUGCAGUAUGCCAAAGCCAAGGAAGCAGAUGGAAGAUACAAAGAAGCUGUUGUAGCUUAUGAAAAUGCAAAACAGUGGCAAAGUGUAAUCCGCAUCUAUCUGGAUCACCUCAAUAAUCCUGAAAAAGCUGUCAAUAUUGUUAGAGAGACCCAGUCUCUGGAUGGAGCCAAAAUGGUAGCCAGGUUUUUUCUACAGCUUGGUGACUAUGGGUCUGCCAUCCAGUUUCUUGUCAUGUCCAAAUGCAACAAUGAAGCUUUCACACUGGCUCAGCAACACAACAAAAUGGAAAUCUAUGCAGAUAUUAUUGGUUCUGAAGACACUACUAAUGAAGACUAUCAAAGCAUUGCCUUAUACUUUGAAGGAGAAAAGAGAUAUCUUCAGGCUGGAAAAUUCUUCUUGCUGUGUGGCCAAUAUUCACGAGCACUUAAACACUUCCUGAAAUGCCCAAGCUCGGAAGAUAAUGUGGCAAUAGAAAUGGCAAUUGAAACUGUUGGUCAGGCCAAAGAUGAACUGCUGACCAAUCAGCUGAUAGACCAUCUCCUGGGGGAGAACGAUGGCAUGCCUAAGGAUGCCAAGUACCUGUUCCGCUUGUACAUGGCUCUGAAGCAAUACCGAGAAGCUGCCCAGACUGCCAUCAUCAUUGCCAGAGAAGAGCAGUCUGCAGGCAACUACCGGAAUGCACACGAUGUUCUCUUCAGUAUGUAUGCAGAACUGAAAUCCCAGAAGAUCAAAAUUCCCUCCGAGAUGGCCACCAACCUCAUGAUUCUGCACAGCUAUAUACUAGUAAAGAUUCAUGUUAAAAAUGGAGAUCACAUGAAAGGGGCUCGCAUGCUCAUUCGGGUGGCCAACAACAUCAGCAAAUUUCCAUCACCAGCUCCAUGAAGUGGUAUGUCAGGGCCCCAAGACCACUCCCAGGUUUGAUGACUCUUCACUGGGAGGAUUUACAAGAGUCAACACACAGUAGUACCAAAGCCGAGAUUUAUCACAGCAAAAGGAUCUGAGGCAAAAUGAGCAGAAGGAUUCACGCAAAGGCGAGCAGGUGCAGGCACGGACCUCCAAGAGUCCCUUCCCAGUGGAGCACACAGGACGCAAGUUCCGUAACUCCUCCACGACUGACUUGUACAACAUGGUGAAACGUAGAGUGCCAAGAAGCUCAUUAGAGACUCAGCAGCCAGGAGUUUUAUUGGGGUGUGGUCACAUAGGUGCCCCCUGCGUGGCAUGUGCCCAGUUUUCCAGGCUCCCAGAGAGCAGGUGUUCGGCAUAAACCACGUUGUUUGUACAAAGAUUUUAGGCACGGUGAGCCACUCAUCAGUUCUGGAAACGGUGGGAACCGUCUCCAAAUCUAUGUUCCAGAUGCGAGCCGAGGGUUAGCUGUUCAAGCCUUUCCAAGGAUGACAGUCUCAGGCCUGCACACACAAGUACUUUUCUGAACAAACUGGGACAAAAGAAAUAACAUUUGCCCAAGAUCACAUUGUCAGCUAAUAAUAGCCUGACUCUGUGUUCACAAGCACGGUAGGACGUUGCCUCUGAAAAGGCCUCACUAUUCCAAAAGACAUGUCAUGAUAACAUUCUUAAGUGAUUAAAUACUGUCACAUUACAUGACAGGGAUCAGCAAACUUUUUCUGUAAAGGACCAGAUGUUAAAUAUUUUAGACUUCGUGAGACAUGUGGCCUCUGUCACAACUGCUCAACUCUGCCAUCUUCUCAUGAAUAAUACGUAAACGAAUGGGCAUGACUGUGUUUCAAUAGAGCUUUAUGUUUGGACACAAAUGUUAACCACAUACACUUUUAACAUGUCACAAAAAUAUUUUUCUUUUGAUGUUUUUUCAACCAUUUAAAAAUGUAAAAAUCAUCCUUAGCUCAUGGACCAUACAAAAAGUCAGAGGGCUAGAUUUGGUCCAUGGGUCAUAAUUGGCCAACCCACAUUCUCUAAGUGUAUUUUUGUUGUUGUUACAUCAAAGUCUACCAUGCGGGCAAGGUAUGGGAUAGGACAGGCACUCUCAUGACUGCUGGUGGGGAUGGAAAUUGGUAUGGCCUUUGCAGAAAGCAGUUUGGCAAUUUGUGGUAAGAGUAUUUUUUAAAAGGUCCUGUUUUUGAGCCGGUAAUUCUGGGUGUCUGUCCUGAAGAAAGAAUUUGAUGCCUGCAGAGAGAUUAGUGUAUAAAGUCAUUAAUCCCCCUAAUGCUUUUAUCAGCAGUCCUGUCAGAUGCAAAAAAUAUCUAAGAGGCAUGAAAGGAAACUCAUGGAAGUGUUGCCUCAAGGGGUGCAGGUCCUAGUGUUACAAGGCAGAACAUGGUGUCAUCAAAGGAAAAGCACUUGAUGGGCAGUUAGCCUGACCCCACAGCUACGUACUUUCCUCAUUAAACAGAUCAUAUCUGGUUCUUUGCAGAAAAAGCAAAGUUCAGAGACCAUGACCCUGUUUUCCUACAGAACCAGGGUGGAAUCCCGCCUGUAUCACUGAGGACAGCAGACACUGUGCUGUUGCUGCUCUCCCCUUUUCUCUUGCAGACAUUGUACCCAUCCUGACGUCAACUGUGAUUGAGUGUCACAGGGCAGGCCUGAAGAACUCUGCUUUCAGCUUCGCAGCUAUGUUGAUGAGGCCUGAAUACCGCAGCAAAAUAGAUGCCAAAUACAAAAAGAAGAUCGAGGGAAUGG